GGAAGGACUUAAGCGCCCCGGAGCCGGGAGGCGAACUUGGGACCCGCUGGCCUCGCUCGGAUCGACCCGUACGGAUUCGAGCGGCCUGAGGACUUCGACGACGCCGCCUACGAGAAGUUUUUCUCCAGCUACCUGGUCACGCUCACCCGCAGGGCGAUCAAAUGGUCCCGGCUGCUGCAGGGCGGGGGCGUCCCCAGGAGCCGGACAGUGAAGCGCUAUGUCCGGAAAGGGGUCCCGCUGGAGCACCGUGCCCGCGUCUGGAUGGUGCUGAGUGGGGCCCAGGCGCAGAUGGACCAGAAUCCCGGCUACUACCACCAGCUUCUCCAGGGAGAGAGAAACCCCAGGCUGGAGGACGCCAUCAGGACAGACCUGAACCGGACCUUCCCCGACAACGUGAAGUUCCGGAAGACCACGGACCCCUGCUUACAGAGGACCCUGUACAAUGUGCUGCUGGCAUAUGGGCACCAUAACCAGGGAGUGGGCUACUGCCAGGGAAUGAAUUUUAUAGCAGGAUAUCUGAUUCUUAUAACAAAUAAUGAAGAAGAAUCUUUUUGGCUGUUAGAUGCUCUUGUUGGAAGAAUACUACCAGAUUACUACAGCCCGGCCAUGCUGGGCCUGAAGACCGACCAGGAGGUCCUCGGGGAGCUGGUGCGGGCGAAGCUGCCGGCUGUGGGGGCCCUGAUGGAGCGUCUCGGUGUGCUGUGGACGCUGCUGGUGUCCCGCUGGUUCAUCUGCCUGUUUGUGGACAUCUUGCCCGUGGAGACAGUGCUUCGGAUCUGGGACUGUUUGUUUAACGAAGGCUCGAAGAUUAUCUUCCGGGUGGCCCUGACCUUAAUUAAGCAGCACCAGGAGUUGAUUUUGGAAGCCACCAGCGUUCCAGACAUUUGCGAUAAGUUUAAGCAGAUAACCAAAGGGAGUUUCGUGAUGGAGUGUCACACGUUUAUGCAGGUGUGUGGGGCUGCACGUGGCUCAGUCCCCUCCCAGGGGGCCCCGCCUCACCUGCAGCCCGGGGGCUGCUCUGACCACCCGGAGGGUGCACAGGACGGGCACCAGUGGGCAUAGGGCACAGGAUGAGCCUCCAGCUCUGUCCUGCAUCUGCCCCCUGCGCCUGGCCUCCGAGGGCUUUCCUGUCUAUGGCGGCCCUGUCUUCUUGGCCCUGGCACUGCGGACGCUGCUCCUGGUCCUAAUGGCUGUACUCAUCUGCUGUGUGUGGUGCCAGAAGUGUGGCUUCCCGAGGCCCGGCCUCCCCACUGGGUCCUGGACCUGGCGCAGGCCGUAUAGACUCAGGUCCUGAUGAGGGCGUUGUGGGAGCUGUACCUGACAGGCCUUCUGAGGAAGCCAAGACGCCAGGAGAGGCUCAGGCCUGGGAGUCAGUAGUUUCCUAAGAGGGAGUGGAGGCUCGGGGCCACUCUGGGUGCAGCAUGGCAAACGUGGGCGGUAUUUCAGCAGCUGGGCCUUCAUCAAAGAGAAGACCAUGUUGGCCGGGCGCGGUGGCUCACGCCUGCAGUCCCAGCACUUUGGGAGGCCAAGGCGUGUGGAUCACCUGAGGUCAGGAGUUCAAGACCAGCCUGGCCAACACGGUGAAACCCCGUCUCUACUAAAAAAUACAAAAAUUAGCCAGGUGUGGUGGCUCACGCUUAUGUAGUCCCAGUUACUCGGGAGGCUGAGGCACGAGAAUCACUUGAACCUGGGAGGCGGAGGUUGCAGUGAGCCGAGAUCGCGCCACUGCACUCCAGCCUGGGCAACAGAGUGAGACUCUGUCUCAAAAAAAAAAAAAAAGUCUAAUGGAAGCAGAUGGCCUUUUCUUCCACCGUUUGAUUCAUUUAACAUUUCUGAGCAGCAAAGCUGCAGUCCUAGGCCCCAGGGCAGGAGUGAGAUGGUGACAAUCUGUGGGUCACCCCAGAAGCCCUUGGAUGUGGACUGCUCCUCCCUCACCUCACACGAGGCCUGUCUGCCUGCCUGCCAGUCUGGGAGAGCUAACGUAGAAAUGGGUUGUUGGGUUUGUUUUUAAACUAACUGUUUGCCUUCCAGAAAAUAUUUUCAGAACCUGGAAGCUUAUCCAUGGCCACCGUCGCCAAGCUCCGCGAGAGCUGCAGGGCCCGGCUGCUGGCACAGGGGUGAGCGUGCCUGUCCCCUGCGUUGCUCGUCUCUACACUGACGAUGCCCCUUUCCAGAGUUGACACUGGACCAACUUUCACUGCUUUCCUUUUUAGUGUUGUAAAUACUUGACAUCACUACACUUUAGUUGUGAAUUUUUUAAAAGAGCAGUUUAAAAUCAGGUCAUUCUACCAGCUUUUGAUGAUUAGCUAUGAAGUCAUACUUUUUAAAGAAAACUUAUUUUUACCUGAGAGAUCAAUAAUAUAUAAAAUGUGAGUGUGGGUUUGUAUCUAAUAAAGUAUGCCAACACCUGU